ACUUUGCGGCAGCGCCGAGAACCCCACCCCCUUUCUUUGCGGAAUCACCAUGGCGGCUGGGACCCUGUACACGUAUCCUGAAAACUGGAGGGCCUUCAAGGCUCUCAUCGCUGCUCAGUACAGCGGGGCUCAGGUCCGCGUGCUCUCCGCACCACCCCACUUCCAUUUUGGCCAAACCAACCGCACCCCUGAAUUUCUCCGCAAAUUUCCUGCCGGCAAGGUCCCAGCAUUUGAGGGUGAUGAUGGAUUCUGUGUGUUUGAGAGCAACGCCAUUGCCUACUAUGUGAGCAAUGAGGAGCUGCGGGGAAGUACUCCAGAGGCAGCAGCCCAGGUGGUGCAGUGGGUGAGCUUUGCUGAUUCCGAUAUAGUGCCCCCAGCCAGUACCUGGGUGUUCCCCACCUUGGGCAUCAUGCACCACAACAAACAGGCCACUGAGAAUGCAAAGGAGGAAGUGAGGCGAAUUCUGGGGCUGCUGGAUGCUUACUUGAAGACGAGGACUUUUCUGGUGGGCGAACGAGUGACAUUGGCUGACAUCACAGUUGUCUGCACCCUGUUGUGGCUCUAUAAGCAGGUUCUAGAGCCUUCUUUCCGCCAGGCCUUUCCCAAUACCAACCGCUGGUUCCUCACCUGCAUUAACCAGCCCCAGUUCCGGGCUGUCUUGGGCGAAGUGAAACUGUGUGAGAAGAUGGCCCAGUUUGAUGCUAAAAAGUUUGCAGAGACCCAACCUAAAAAGGACACACCACGGAAAGAGAAGGGUUCACGGGAAGAGAAGCAGAAGCCCCAGGCUGAGCGGAAGGAGGAGAAAAAGGCGGCUGCCCCUGCUCCUGAGGAGGAGAUGGAUGAAUGUGAGCAGGCGCUGGCUGCUGAGCCCAAGGCCAAGGACCCCUUCGCUCACCUGCCCAAGAGUACCUUUGUGUUGGAUGAAUUUAAGCGCAAGUACUCCAAUGAGGACACACUCUCUGUGGCACUGCCAUAUUUCUGGGAGCACUUUGAUAAGGACGGCUGGUCCCUGUGGUACUCAGAGUAUCGCUUCCCUGAAGAACUCACUCAGACCUUCAUGAGCUGCAAUCUCAUCACUGGAAUGUUCCAGCGACUGGACAAGCUGAGGAAGAAUGCCUUCGCCAGUGUCAUCCUUUUUGGAACCAACAAUAGCAGCUCCAUUUCUGGAGUCUGGGUCUUCCGAGGCCAGGAGCUUGCCUUUCCGCUGAGUCCAGAUUGGCAGGUGGACUACGAGUCAUACACAUGGCGGAAACUGGAUCCUGGCAGCGAGGAGACCCAGACGCUGGUUCGAGAGUACUUUUCCUGGGAGGGGGCCUUCCAGCAUGUGGGCAAAGCCUUCAAUCAGGGCAAGAUCUUCAAGUGAACAUCUCUUGCCAUCACCUAGCUGCCUGCACCUGCCCUUCAGGGAGAUGGGGGUCAUUAAAGGAAACUGAACAUUGAACCCUU